GUGCGCCUGCGCUGCGCUAGGGCGCGGCGGGCGGUUUGAAUUUUGCUUACAGAGUCCCGUCUCACCAUCCUGGGCUUCCAACGGAGACUGCGGUAUCCGCAGCUGGAGACCCAGCGGCGAGUAGCCUUUUGCUCCCGGACGGACUUGAGGUUGGAGUCUGUGUGUUGGGGACCCUGCCUUUGGAAGCGCCCGAGAGGCUUAAAGGAUGGCCUCGUCAGAUCUGGAACAAUUAUGCUCUCAUGUUAAUGAAAAGAUUGGCAAUAUUAAGAAAACCUUAUCAUUAAGAAACUGUGGCCAGGAACCUACCUUGAAAACUGUAUUAAAUAAAAUAGGAGAUGAGAUCAUUGUAAUAAAUGAACUUCUAAAUAAAUUGGAAUUGGAAAUUCAGUAUCAAGAACAAACCAACAAUUCACUCAAGGAACUCUGUGAAUCUCUUGAAGAAGAUUACAAAGACAUAGAACAUCUUAAAGAAAACGUUCCUUCCCAUUUGCCUCAAGUAACAGUAACCCAGAGCUGUGUUAAGGGAUCAGAUCUUGAUCCUGAAGAACCAAUCAAAGUUGAAGAACCUGAACCCGUAAAGAAGCCUCCCAAAGAGCAAAGAAGUAUUAAGGAAAUGCCAUUUAUAACUUGUGAUGAGUUCAAUGGUGUUCCUUCGUACAUGAAAUCCCGCUUAACCUAUAAUCAAAUUAAUGAUGUUAUUAAAGAAAUCAACAAGGCAGUAAUUAGUAAAUAUAAAAUCCUACAUCAGCCAAAAAAGUCUAUGAAUUCUGUGACCAGAAAUCUCUAUCACAGAUUUAUUGAUGAAGAAACGAAGGAUACCAAAGGUCGUUAUUUUAUAGUGGAAGCUGACAUAAAGGAGUUCACAACUUUGAAAGCUGACAAGAAGUUUCACGUGUUACUGAAUAUUUUACGACACUGCCGGAGGCUAUCAGAGGUCCGAGGGGGAGGACUUACUCGUUAUGUUAUAACCUGAGUCCCUUGUGAACUUUUGAACAUACCAACAGGGUAUAGAGUAUAGAGGCUAUUUCUAUAAUUUUCUUAUAUAUAAUUUUUUUAACUUUUAAUCUUUUUUGUUUCCUUUUUUUUUUUUUUGAGACAGGAUCUUGCUUUGUCACCCAGGGGCUUGCUUUGUCACGCAGGCUAGAGUGCAGUGGCGCAAACAUGGCUCACUGCAGCCUCAACCUCCCAGGCUCAAGUGAUCCUCCCACCUCAGCCCCCUGAAUGGCUGGGACUACAAGCGUGCGCCACCAUGCCUGGCUAAUUUUUGUAUUUUUUGGAGAGAUGGGGUUUCACCAUGUUGCCUAGGCUGGUCUUGAGCUCCUGAGCUCAAACAAUCCACCCUCCUCAGCCUCCCAAAGUGCUGGGAUUACAGGCUUGAGCCACCACACCUGACCUAUUCUUGUUUCUUAUAAAAAUAAAACUUUUUUGGAUAAAGCUUAUUUCUUGUUUUUUUCUUUUUCUUUUUUUUUUUUUUUGAGACAGUCUCGCUCUUUCACCCAGGCCGGACUGCAGCGGCGCUAUCUCGGCUCACUGCAAACUCUGCCUCCCAGGUUCACGCCAUCCUCCUGCCUCAGCCUCCUGAGUAGCUGGGACUACAGGCACCUGCCACCACGCCCAGCUAAUUUUUUGUAUUUUUAGUAGAGAUGGGGUUUCACCGUGUUAGCCAGGAUGGUCUCGAUCUCCUGACCUCAUGAUCCGCCCACCUCGGCCUCCCAAAGUGCUGGGAUUACAGGCGUGAGCCACCGCGCCCGGCCAACUUAUAUAUUUUCAAGAUUCACCUCCUCUCACCAAAUAUUUAACUACCUGCUGAAUACGCCUCUGUACUAGGCACAUAAUGGAACUAAAAAAUGCUCAUGUCCAGUUUUUGUGUUGAGUGAACAAUGCUGCAGACCCUAAUAAGAUUGGGUACAGAUCGGCAUGCGCCUGUAGUCCCAGCUACUCAGGAGAAUUGCUUGAACCUAGGAGGUGGAGGUUGCAGUGAGCCGAGAUCGUGCCACUGCACUCCAGUCUGGGCAACAGAGCGAGACUCCAUCUCAGAAAAAAAGAAAAAAAGACUGGGUACAGAUGUGAUAUUGGAAGAAAAAGAUCAAGCUGAUGAGGUUAGGAUACCCAGGCCCUUUGGACUUAAAGAUCACUAGUGUCUAAAUUCCAUCGAUGGCAUUUCAGUCUAUAGGUAAACUUCCUGGAAGCUGGAUUUGGAGACAGUUUAUCAUCUGAUUAUUGGGCUUUCGUAUAGGUCCUUAGGGAGCAGCUUACCUGAAAUGCAUUUAGUGUACACCAGUCUGUAAACUUCAACCUGUAAUGAAAGUGUAAUAAAUGUACAUUGAGUUGAUGUGAUAAUGUGAUAUAAUAAGAAAUAUAUAUUUGAUCUUCCUAUCUAGUUCCUUGUUCAGAGCUCCUAAAACCCUUGUAAUUUCCAAAGUGAUGGAGUACAUCUUUUGUUCUAGUAUUUGGUCUUUGACCCCAGUUCCUGACACAAAGCUCCUAAAUUCCUUUAAAUUUCCCAGUGAUAGGAGAAUUUUUUGUUCUAAUGAGGUCACUCUUGAUGGGCACCUGGAUAACUCAGGAUGGGGGCUGCUCACAAAGACCACAUCAUGAUUGGAAGUUUCAAACUUUCAGUCUCCCACCUCCAGAGAGGGGAGAGGGGCUGGAGAUUUGUGUCAAUAAUCCAUCAGGCCUAUGUCAACAAGACAUAAUCCGUUAACUAUGGAGUUCAGGGAGCUUCAGGGUUGGCAAACAUUUUGAUGUGCCAGGAAGGUGACGCACUCCAGCUUUAUGAAGUCAGCAAGUCCUGUGCUCAGGAUGCUUCUGGACCUUGCCCCAGGUACCCCUUCAUGUGGCUGUUGUUCAUCUGUAUCCUUUGUAGUAGCCUUAAAAUAAACUGUUAAACACAA